AUUCUGCGCCUGCGCGCGGCUACAGCACGGUUCGUUUUUCCUUUAGUCAGGAAGGACGUUGGUGUUGAGGUGAGUCCGGUCCCUUUUGCAUCCCUACCCCGACACUGCGGGUUGUCACAACGGCACCCUCCCGCUUUCUCUCUGCCUCGGAUUUAGUCGUGACUGUGUGUCUCCGCCGUGGUGCAGCUUCAGGCCUCUCCCGCAUCUACUCUCUCACGCUUCCGCUGCGGCCUGAGGGAGGGCGGCGGGCGGACCACGGACCGGGGUUAGCAUACGUAUCAAGGACAGUAACUACCAUGGCUCCCGAAGUUUUGCCAAAACCUCGGAUGCGUGGCCUUCUGGCCAGGCGUCUGCGAAAUCAUAUGGCUGUAGCAUUCGUGCUAUCCCUGGGGGUUGCAGCUUUGUAUAAGUUUCGUGUGGCUGAUCAAAGAAAGAAGGCAUACGCAGAUUUCUACAGAAACUACGAUGUCAUGAAAGAUUUUGAGGAGAUGAGGAAGGCUGGUAUCUUUCAGAGUGUAAAGUAAUCUUGGAAUAUAAAGAAUUUCUUCAGGUUGAAUUACCUAGAAGUUUGUCACUGACUUGUGUUCCUGAACUAUGACACAUGAAUAUGUGGGCUAAGAAAUAGUUCCUCUUGAUAAAUAAACAAUUAACAAAUACUUUGGACAGUAAGUCUUUCUCAGUUCUUAAUGAUAAUGCAGGGCACUUACUAGCAUAAGAAUUGGUUUGGGAUUUAACUGUUUAUGAAGCUAACUUGAUUUCCGUGUUUUGUUAAAAUUUCAUUGUUCUAGCACAUCUUUAACUGUGAUAGUUUGUCCGUUUCAUUGCAGUUACUUGGUCUUGGGCUAUGGAUUAAAAAGUGUUCUUCAUGAGCCUGUAAGACUACUGUACUGUGGGCUCUAAGAAGAGAUAGAAUCCUAAUAAAAUCUAUCCUUGGCCUUCA